CCUUCCUCUCCUAGCCUAAGGCGUGCAAACAGAGCGCCACUGGGAGGCUGAAACCUUUAGGCCGAUGCUUGCUUGCAAGGUCAGGCAAGCUGGAUUCUGGUCCCCACCUUUGCAGAGAGAACAGCGAUGUUGUGCGCCCAUUUCUCAGAUCAAGGACCGGCCCAUCUUACUACCUCCAAGAGUGCUUUUCUCUCUAAUAAGAAAACAUCUACUUUGAAACAUCUACUGGGCGAGACCAGGAGUGAUGGCUCAGCCUGUAAUUCUGGAAUUUCGGGAGGCCGAGGCAGGAAGAUUCCUUGAGCACAGGAGUUCCAGACCAGCCUGGGCAAUGUAGCAAGACGCUGUCUCUAUUUAUACAAUAAAAUUUUUUUAAAAAAGGAAA